GAUACGGGAUCCUUCUCUCUUGAGCCGGCAGAGCCCUGGGGAGCCAGCUGCACCAGGAGCUCUUGGCCGUCCUUCCUGUUCUCCUCUCCGCAGGUCCAGCACCGCCGCAGCCACUUCCUUCUGUGGAGCAGCAGGUGCUGGGGCUAAAGUGCCCAGAGGUGUCCCUGGAGGCCCCUGUGAGCCCAGCCAGCGCAGUGCGCACCACCCUCUUAGGCAACAGGAGCAGCACAAGAACCUGCUAUGGGCUUCUUGCCCAAGCUUCUCCUCCUGGCCUCAUUCUUCCCAGCAGGCCAGGCCUCAUGGGGCGUCUCCAGUCCCCAGGACGUGCAGGGUGUGAAGGGGUCUUGCCUGCUUAUCCCCUGCAUCUUCAGCUUCCCUGCCGACGUGGAGGUGCCCGACGGCAUCACGGCCAUCUGGUACUACGACUACUCGGGCCAGCGGCAGGUGGUGAGCCACUCGGCGGACCCCAAGCUGGUGGAGGCCCGCUUCCGCGGCCGCACCGAGUUCAUGGGGAACCCCGAGCACAGGGUGUGCAACCUGCUGCUGAAGGACCUGCAGCCCGAGGACUCUGGUUCCUACAACUUCCGCUUCGAGAUCAGUGAGGUCAACCGCUGGUCAGAUGUGAAAGGCACCUUGGUCACAGUAACAGAGGAGCCCAGGGUGCCCACCAUUGCCUCCCCGGUGGAGCUUCUCGAGGGCACAGAGGUGGACUUCAACUGCUCCACUCCCUACGUAUGCCUGCAGGAGCAGGUCAGACUGCAGUGGCAAGGCCAGGACCCUGCUCGCUCUGUCACCUUCAACAGCCAGAAGUUUGAGCCCACCGGCGUCGGCCACCUGGAGACCCUCCACAUGGCCAUGUCCUGGCAGGACCACGGCCGGAUCCUGCGCUGCCAGCUCUCCGUGGCCAAUCACAGGGCUCAGAGCGAGAUUCACCUCCAAGUGAAGUAUGCCCCCAAGGGUGUGAAGAUCCUCCUCAGCCCCUCGGGGAGGAACAUCCUUCCAGGUGAGCUGGUCACACUCACCUGCCAGGUGAACAGCAGCUACCCUGCAGUCAGUUCCAUUAAGUGGCUCAAGGAUGGGGUACGCCUCCAAACCAAGACUGGUGUGCUGCACCUGCCCCAGGCAGCCUGGAGCGAUGCUGGCGUCUACACCUGCCAAGCUGAGAACGGCGUGGGCUCUUUGGUCUCACCCCCCAUCAGCCUCCACAUCUUCAUGGCUGAGGUCCAGGUGAGCCCAGCAGGUCCCAUCCUGGAGAACCAGACAGUGACACUAGUCUGCAACACACCCAAUGAGGCACCCAGUGAUCUCCGCUACAGCUGGUACAAGAACCAUGUCCUGCUGGAGGAUGCCCACUCCCAUACCCUCCGGCUGCACUUGGCCACUAGGGCUGAUACUGGCUUCUACUUCUGUGAGGUGCAGAACGUCCAUGGCAGCGAGCGCUCGGGCCCUGUCAGCGUGGUAGUCAACCACCCGCCUCUCACUCCAGUCCUGACAGCCUUCCUGGAGACCCAGGCGGGACUUGUGGGCAUCCUUCACUGCUCUGUGGUCAGUGAGCCCCUGGCCACACUGGUGCUGUCACAUGGGGGUCAUAUCCUGGCCUCCACCUCCGGGGACAGUGAUCACAGCCCACGCUUCAGUGGUACCUCUGGUCCCAACUCCCUGCGCCUGGAGAUCCGAGACCUGGAGGAAACUGACAGUGGGGAGUACAAGUGCUCAGCCACCAACUCCCUUGGAAAUGCAACCUCCACCCUGGACUUCCAUGCCAAUGCCGCCCGUCUCCUCAUCAGCCCGGCAGCCGAGGUGGUGGAAGGACAGGCAGUGACACUGAGCUGCAGAAGCGGCCUAAGCCCCACACCUGAUGCCCGCUUCUCCUGGUACCUGAAUGGAGCCCUGCUUCACGAGGGUCCCGGCAGCAGCCUCCUGCUCCCCGCGGCCUCCAGCACUGACGCCGGCUCAUACCACUGCCGGGCCCGGGACGGCCACAGUGCCAGUGGCCCCUCUUCGCCAGCUGUUCUCACUGUGCUCUACCCCCCUCGACAACCAACAUUCACCACCAGGCUGGACCUUGAUGCCGCUGGGGCCGGGGCUGGACGGCGAGGCCUCCUUUUGUGCCGUGUGGACAGCGACCCCCCCGCCAGGCUGCAGCUGCUCCACAAGGACCGUGUUGUGGCCACUUCCCUGCCAUCAGGGGGUGGCUGCAGCACCUGUGGGGGCUGUUCCCCACGCAUGAAGGUCACCAAAGCCCCCAACUUGCUGCGUGUGGAGAUUCACAACCCUUUGCUGGAAGAGGAGGGCUUGUACCUCUGUGAGGCCAGCAAUGCCCUGGGCAACGCCUCCACCUCAGCCACCUUCAAUGGCCAGGCCACUGUCCUGGCCAUUGCACCAUCACACACACUUCAGGAGGGCACAGAAGCCAACUUGACUUGCAACGUGAGCCGGGAAGCUGCUGGCAGCCCUGCUAACUUCUCCUGGUUCCGAAAUGGGGUGCUGUGGGCCCAGGGUCCCCUGGAGACCGUGACACUGCUGCCCGUGGCCAGAACUGAUGCUGCCCUUUACGCCUGCCGCAUCCUGACUGAGGCUGGUGCCCAGCUCUCCACUCCCGUGCUCCUGAGUGUACUCUAUCCCCCGGACCGUCCAAAGCUGUCAGCCCUCCUAGACAUGGGCCAGGGCCACAUGGCUCUGUUCAUCUGCACUGUGGACAGCCGCCCCCUGGCCUUGCUGGCCUUGUUCCAUGGGGAGCACCUCCUGGCCACCAGCCUGGGUCCCCAGGUCCCAUCCCAUGGUCGGUUCCAGGCUAAAGCUGAGGCCAACUCCCUGAAGUUAGAGGUCCGAGAACUGGGCCUUGGGGACUCUGGCAGCUACCGCUGUGAGGCCACAAAUGUUCUUGGAUCAUCCAACACCUCACUCUUCUUCCAGGUCCGAGGAGCCUGGGUCCAGGUGUCACCAUCACCUGAGCUCCAAGAGGGCCAGGCUGUGGUCCUGAGCUGCCAGGUACACACAGGAGUCCCAGAGGGGACCUCAUAUCGUUGGUAUCGGGAUGGCCAGCCCCUCCAGGAGUCGACCUCGGCCACGCUCCGCUUUGCAGCCAUAACUUUGACACAAGCUGGGGCCUAUCAUUGCCAAGCCCAGGCCCCAGGCUCAGCCACCACGAGCCUAGCUGCACCCAUCAGCCUCCACGUGUCCUAUGCCCCACGCCACGUCACACUCACUACCCUGAUGGACACAGGCCCUGGACGACUGGGCCUCCUCCUGUGCCGUGUGGACAGUGACCCUCCGGCCCAGCUGCGGCUGCUCCACGGGGAUCGCCUUGUGGCCUCCACCCUACAAGGUGUGGGGGGACCCGAAGGCAGCUCUCCCAGGCUGCAUGUGGCUGUGGCCCCCAACACACUGCGUCUGGAGAUCCACGGGGCUAUGCUGGAGGAUGAGGGUGUCUAUAUCUGUGAGGCCUCCAACACCCUGGGCCAGGCCUCGGCCUCAGCUGACUUCGACGCUCAAGCUGUGAAUGUGCAGGUGUGGCCCGGGGCUACCGUGCGGGAGGGGCAGCUGGUGAACCUGACCUGCCUUGUGUGGACCACUCACCCGGCCCAGCUCACCUACACAUGGUACCAGGAUGGGCAGCAGCGCCUGGAUGCCCACUCCAUCCCCCUGCCCAACGUCACAGUCAGGGAUGCCACCUCCUACCGCUGCGGUGUGGGCCCCCCUGGUCGGGCACCCCGCCUCUCCAGACCUAUCACCUUGGACGUCCUCUACGCGCCCCGCAACCUGCGCCUGACCUACCUCCUGGAGAGCCAUGGCGGGCAGCUGGCCCUGGUACUGUGCACUGUGGACAGCCGCCCGCCCGCCCAGCUGGCCCUCAGCCACGCCGGUCGCCUCUUGGCCUCCUCGACAGCAGCCUCUGUCCCCAACACCCUGCGCCUGGAGCUGCGAGGGCCACAGCCCAGGGAUGAGGGUUUCUACAGCUGCUCUGCCCGCAGCCCUCUGGGCCAGGCCAACACGUCCCUGGAGCUGCGGCUGGAGGGUGUGCGGGUGAUCCUGGCUCCGGAGGCUGCCGUGCCUGAAGGUGCCCCCAUCACAGUGACCUGUGCGGACCCUGCUGCCCACGCACCCACACUCUAUACUUGGUACCACAACGGUCGUUGGCUGCAGGAGGGUCCAGCUGCCUCACUCUCAUUCCUGGUGGCCACGCGGGCUCAUGCAGGCGCCUACUCUUGCCAGGCCCAGGAUGCCCAGGGCACCCGCAGCUCCCGUCCUGCUGCCCUGCAAGUCCUCUAUGCCCCUCAGGACGCUGUCCUGUCCUCCUUCCGGGACUCCAGGGCCAGAUCCAUGGCUGUGAUACAGUGCACUGUGGACAGUGAGCCACCUGCUGAGCUGGCCCUAUCUCAUGAUGGCAAGGUGCUGGCCACGAGCAGCGGGGUCCACAGCUUGGCAUCAGGGACAGGCCAUGUCCAGGUGGCCCGAAACGCCCUACGGCUGCAGGUGCAAGAUGUGCCUGCAGGUGAUGACACCUAUGUUUGCACAGCCCAAAACUUGCUGGGCUCAAUCAGCACCAUCGGGCGGUUGCAGGUAGAAGGUGCACGCGUGGUGGCAGAGCCUGGCCUGGACGUGCCUGAGGGCGCUGCCCUGAACCUCAGCUGCCGCCUCCUGGGUGGCCCUGGGCCUGUGGGCAACUCCACCUUUGCAUGGUUCUGGAAUGACCGGCGGCUGCACGCGGAGCCUGUGCCCACUCUCGCCUUCACCCACGUGGCUCGUGCUCAAGCUGGGAUGUACCACUGCCUGGCUGAGCUCCCCACUGGGGCUGCUGCCUCUGCUCCAGUCAUGCUCCGUGUGCUCUACCCUCCCAAGACGCCCACCAUGAUGGUCUUCGUGGAGCCUGAGGGUGGCCUCCGGGGCAUCCUGGAUUGCCGAGUGGACAGCGAGCCGCUCGCCAGCCUGACUCUCCACCUUGGCAGUCGACUGGUGGCCUCCAGUCAGCCCCAGGGUGCUCCUGCAGAGCCACACAUCCAUGUCCUGGCUUCCCCCAAUGCCCUGAGGGUGGACAUCGAGGCGCUGAGGCCCAGCGACCAAGGGGAAUACAUCUGUUCUGCCUCAAAUGUCCUGGGCUCUGCCUCUACCUCCACCUACUUUGGGGUCAGAGCCCUGCACCGCCUGCAUCAGUUCCAGCAGCUGCUCUGGGUCCUGGGACUGCUGGUGGGCCUCCUGCUCCUGCUGUUGGGCCUGGGGGCCUGCUACACCUGGAGAAGGAGGCGUGUUUGUAAGCAGAGCAUGGGCGAGAAUUCGGUGGAGAUGGCUUUUCAGAAAGAGACCACGCAGCUCAUUGAUCCUGAUGCAGCCACAUGUGAGACCUCAACCUGUGCCCCACCCCUGGGCUGACCAGUGGUGUUGCCUGCCCUCCGGAGGAGAAAGUGGCCAGAAUCUGUGAUGACUCCAGCCUAUGAAUGUGAAUGAGGCAGUGUUGAGUCCUGCCCGCCUCUACGAAAACAGCUCUGUGACAUCUGACUUUUUAUGACCUGGCCCCAAGCCUCUUGCCCCCCCAAAAAUGGGUGGUGAGAGGUCUGCCCAGGAGGGUGUUGACCCUGGAGGACACUGAAGAGCACUGAGCUGAUCUCGCUCUCUCUUCUCUGGAUCUCCUCCCUUCUCUCCAUUUCUCCCUCAAAGGAAGCCCUGCCCUUUCACAUCCUUCUCCUCGAAAGUCACCCUGGACUUUGGUUGGAUUGCAGCAUCCUGCAUCCUCAGAGGCUCACCAAGGCAUUCUGUAUUCAACAGAGUAUCAGUCAGCCUGCUCUAACAAGAGACCAAAUACAGUGACUUCAACAUGAUAGAAUUUUAUUUUUCUCUCCCACGCUAGUCUGGCUGUUACGAUGGUUUAUGAUGUUGGGGCUCAGGAUCCUUCUAUCUUCCUUUUCUCUAUCCCUAAAAUGAUGCCUUUGAUUGUGAGGCUCACCAUGGCCCCGCUUUGUCCACAUGCCCUCCAGCCAGAAGAAGGAAGAGUGGAGGUAGAAGCACACCCAUGCCCAUGGUGGACGCAACUCAGAAGCUGCACAGGACUUUUCCACUCACUUCCCAUUGGCUGGAGUAUUGUCACAUGGCUACUGCAAGCUACAAGGGAGACUGGGAAAUGUAGUUUUUAUUUUGAGUCCAGAGGACAUUUGGAAUUGGACUUCCAAAGGACUCCCAACUGUGAGCUCAUCCCUGAGACUUUUGACAUUGUUGGGAAUGCCACCAGCAGGCCAUGUUUUGUCUCAGUGCCCAUCUACUGAGGGCCAGGGUGUGCCCCUGGCCAUUCUGGUUGUGGGCUUCCUGGAAGAGGUGAUCACUCUCACACUAAGACUGAGGAAAUAAAAAAGGUUUGGUGUUUUCCUAGGGAGAGAGCAUGCCAGGCAGUGGAGUUGCCUAAGCAGACAUCCUUGUGCCAGAUUUGGCCCCUGAAAGAAGAGAUGCCCUCAUUCCCACCACCACCCCCCCUACCCCCAGGGACUGGGUACUACCUUACUGGCCCUUACAAGAGUGGAGGGCAGACACAGAUGUUGUCAGCAUCCUUAUUCCUGCUCCAGAUGCAUCUCUGUUCAUGACUGUGUGAGCUCCUGUCCUUUUCCUGGAGACCCUGUGUCGGGCUGUUAAAGAGAAUGAGUUACCAAGAAGGAAUGACGUGCCCCUGCGAAUCAGGGACCAACAGGAGAGAGCUCUUGAGUGGGCUAGUGACUCCCCCUGCAGCCUGGUGGAGAUGGUGUGAGGAGCGAAGAGCCCUCUGCUCUAGGAUUUGGGUUGAAAAACAGAGAGAGAAGUGGGGAGUUGCCACAGGAGCUAACACGCUGGGAGGCAGUUGGGGGCGGGUGAACUUUGUGUAGCCGAGGCCGCACCCUCCCUCAUUCCAGGCUCAUUCAUUUUCAUGCUCCAUUGCCAGACUCUUGCUGGGAGCCCGUCCAGAAUGUCCUCCCAAUAAAACUCCAUCCUAUGACGCAA